GGUACCGUGGGAGGGGCCGCGCGUGGGGCAGCGGGGAGCGAGUCCCUCCGUCCCCGCGAGUCGGCGCUUUUGGCCCCGCGGGAGGGGCCGGGCUCGAUGAGAAAAGCAUCAUUCAAGCUCAGAUUCGUGUUGAAGCCUGCCACAAGGUCCACCUGUUGUUGUGGGUUUUUGGGUGACCAGGGGUUACCCCCAGCAGUGUGUGAGAAUGAAGAGUGUGGGCCACUGUGUCUCUGUUGACCUGCCAGAUAGGAAAUAGCGCCAGAGUUGCUGCAAUCCACGUCUCCCUGGAAUUCAGGAGCAGCUUGGCUGGAAGGCUCUGGCUGGAAACUUGCAGAAGGCUGUCAGCUGGGUCUGCAUCAUCUGAAGGCUCAACGGGUACCGGGGGCCACUCCAUGGCCUGCGAGUCAGAGCUGGCCGUCGGUGGGAGGCCUCAGUUCCUCUCCACAUAGGCCUCUCCACAGGGCCACUUGAGCGUCUUCCCACCAUGGCAACUGGUGUCCUCUAGAGCAACAUCCAGGAGACCAAGGCGGAAGCAGCUGUAGUGCCUUCCAAGACCUGGUCCUGAAAGUCACCCCUGCACCCACCCCCGCUGUCUCCUCAGCCAUAUUCUGCUGGUCACACAGAGCGCUGCGGGAUAAAGGAGGAGCGUCCUGCUUCCCGGCUGCCCUGUUGCUGUCGGAGUCACAGGAUGGCGGCUGUCAUCCUGCCCUCGACUGCUGCUCCGUCUUCCCUGUUCCCAGCCUCUCAGCAAAAAGGACACACACAGGGCGGAGAGCUGGUUAAUGAGCUCCUGACAAGCUGGCUACGGGGCUUGGUAACCUUCGAGGAUGUGGCCGUGGAGUUCACCCAGGAGGAGUGGGCGUUGCUGGACCCUGCCCAAAGGACACUGUACAGGGAUGUGAUGCUGGAGAACUGCAGGAACCUGGCCUCACUAGGGUGUCGUGUUAAUAAACCCAGUCUGAUAUCCCAGUUGGAACAAGACAAGAAGGUGGUGACAGAGGAAAGAGGAAUUCUACCAAGCACCUGUCCAGAUUUGGAGACUCUACUUAAAGCCAAAUGGUUAACUCCUAAGAAGAAUGUUUUCAGAAAAGAACAGUCUAAAGGUGUAAAAACGGAAAGAAGUCAUCGUGGAGUGAAACUCAAUGAAUGUAAUCAGUGUUUUAAAGUCUUCAGCACGAAAUCUAACCUAACUCAGCACAAGAGAAUUCAUACUGGAGAAAAACCCUAUGACUGUAGUCAAUGUGGGAAGUCCUUCAGUAGCAGAUCUUACCUUACUAUUCAUAAGAGAAUCCAUAAUGGGGAGAAACCCUAUGAAUGCAAUCACUGUGGGAAAGCAUUUAGUGAUCCCUCAUCCCUUAGACUGCAUUUGAGAAUUCACACUGGAGAAAAACCCUAUGAAUGUAACCAGUGUUUUCACGUUUUCCGCACCAGUUGUAACCUCAAAAGCCACAAGAGGAUUCACACGGGGGAGAAUCACCAUGAAUGUAAUCAGUGUGGAAAAGCUUUCAGCACAAGGUCCUCUCUCACUGGGCACAAUAGCAUUCAUACAGGGGAGAAACCUUAUGAAUGUCACGAUUGUGGGAAAACCUUCAGGAAGAGCUCCUAUCUGACACAGCACGUAAGAACUCAUACUGGAGAAAAACCCUAUGAAUGUAACGAGUGUGGGAAAUCCUUCAGCAGUAGCUUUUCUCUUACUGUGCACAAGAGAAUACAUACCGGAGAGAAACCCUACGAGUGCAGUGACUGUGGAAAAGCCUUUAAUAAUCUCUCAGCUGUGAAGAAACACUUAAGAACUCACACUGGAGAAAAACCCUAUGAAUGUAAUCAUUGUGGGAAAUCCUUCACAAGUAACUCCUAUCUUUCUGUGCACAAGAGAAUACAUAAUAGAUGGAUAUGAAUUACUGCAGGAACUUCUGGAGGAAAGCACUCAUUGAUCUUUCAUCCCUAAGAUAGUUUGAGAGAGCUCACACUGGAUAUAUAAGUUAUUUGUUGCAGCAUAACAAAUGAUCCCCGCAAAUUUUGUGGCUUCAAACACGAAAUGUUUAUUCUCUAACAAUUUCUACAGAUCAGGAAUUCAAGAACAGCUUAUCUCUGUAGUUACACUGCAGGAUCUCUCAUGCCUUUACUUACAAUCAAGAUGUCAGCCAAAGCUAUAGUCAUCUAACAUCUUUACUGAUGAACAGUCCACUUCCAAGAUGACUUAUUCACAUGCCUGGAAAGUUGAUGUUGGUUGUUGUCAGGGGACCUUCAGUCAUUACCAUGUAGGCCUCUUUACAAGGCCCAGCUCCUUGACAAUUUGGCAAUAAGUUCUCGCCAAGGUUAGUGAUCCAAGAGAGGACCAAUACAGAGGCCAAAAUGGCUUUUAUGACCUAUCCUCAGGAGGACUGCUAAGCUUUCACUUAUUUCCUAUUGUGUUGGUCUCACAACACACCAAUCCUGAUACAAUGUGAGAGACUGCAGAAGGUAUGAAUACCAGGAAACAGAUAACUCAGAAGCAUCUGGGAAAUUUGCCAUGGAAUUAAUGAAGAAAAGCCCUCAGCACAUCAUCCUUCUACUCUAAUCAAUAUGAAAUAGCAUUCAGUAACUCCUAUUAAUUCACUCUGAAGAGAAACCUUUUGAGGACAAUCUGUAUGGUAAAGCUCUCAGCUCGAAUUCUCACCUUCAUGGGCCCAGAAGAUUAUGUACUGAGAGAAUCCUGAAGAAUGGAACAGCUGUAGAAAGCCUUCAGUGCUAUCAGCAGGGAUUCAUGUGACAGCUCACACUAAGGGAGAAAACCUGUGAAGGUCUCAGAAGGCUUCAGUGACAGUCAUCCCUUAAGACGCACUGGAAAUCACACAAUGGAACAACACUCAGAAAUGCGGAAUACCCUACAGCAAAAGUGUUCACAUUACUGAGCAAACUAUAGUGUGGUAUUCUGCAGUGACUAUGGGAAAGCCUUGAAUGUUCUAUCGGUUUUUAAGGGACUUGAGAAUUAAUUCUGGAGAGAAUGCCCCAUUGAACAUCAUCAAUAUUGGAGAGCUUUCUGUUUUUCUACAUUUGUUAGGAAACUUGUGAGCAUUCACACUACAGAGAAACUUGAAAUAUAAAGAAGAAGAGAAAGCCUUCAGUGAUGCCUCUGUGUUAGGGAAAAUAUGGAACUUCUCCCUGGAUGCAAAACCUAUGAGUAUAUUAAUAUUGGAAAAUUUUUCAGUGAUUCUUCUCUUUCUUGUAUAUGAGAGAACUUAUAUGGAGAAACCCCUAGGAAUGUAAUCAGUGUUAGGAUGCCUCAGCCUGAACUCUUCACUGAGUGGCCACAAUUUUCACUGGGAACAAAAAGUAUAAUCACUGUUUUGAGUGUGGGAUAUCCUUUAUCAGUGUCUCAUCUGUAGAUUGGACUGCUGGCUCAUUAAUUUUUUUAGUCUUUUUUUCUUUUAAUAUAAACAUUUGUGUAUAGCUGUUCCCUAAAAUAAACAUUAACAUAUUUCAUAAUUUUAAUGCAAUGUAUUUAUUAUAAUUAAUUUGCUUGUUAAAGACAUCCACACAUUGCAUAUUCAAAAAGUUAUUUCCAAAUACCUUCUGAGUGAUUCAGUUUAUCAUAAUGGAAAUUAGUAUUUAUAAACACAUUUUUCUAAUGUAGUGGUAUUUUUGGCAGAGUACAUGAGCUUUAUGAUACUGAUUAUUUUCUCUCUAUCUUGGUAUGCCAAAUACUGUUGGUUUCUUUCCCAGUGUCCGUUCUCUUCAGUUUAUUCGUUUAAAGAAACAAACAUGUUGUUCAAGUUGUCUGUGAACAAUAUCGAAAGUUCUCAAUCUUAUAGUUUUUCCUGAAGCCCAGGCGGGUUUUUUCGCACUCCCCUGGCAAUGAGAAGUAAGUCGAAGUCACUGUGUGGAACAUCUCCUGGCUUGUUCUCCUCACAUAUUUUCCAUUCACCUCACCCAUUCUGUCUCUUGGAAAGUGGCCUCAAGGUCUAGAGUUUGAAGAGCUUCUUUUUGACCACAAUGACAGAAACCAAAGUGCAGCCAAAAAUCACAAUGCUUUGGGCUCUCCAGGAGCCUCCGAUUGGCUGCAUCUGCUCUGGACUCCUUAUUCUUAUACUUCUUAUGUGACUAAAAGAAACCCCUAGGCUGGGUGUGGUGGCUCACGCCUUUAAUCCCAGCACUUUUGAGAGGCUGAGGUGGGUGGAUCAUGAGGUCAACAGAUUGAGACCAUCCUGGCCAACGUGGUGAAACCCUAUCUCUACUAAAAGUAUAAAGAUUAGCUGGGUGUGGUGGUGCACACCUGUAUUCCCAGCUACUCGGGAAACUGAGACAGGAGAAUUGCCUGAACCUGGGAGGUAGAGGUUGCAGUGAGCCAAGAUGGCGCCAGUGCACUCCAGCCUGGCAACAGAGCGAGACUCCAUCUCAAAAUAAACAAAUAAAUAUUUUUAAAAAAAGAAACCCCUAACUGAUUGAAGCCAACAUGAUCUGUUGUUUGUUUUUGAGGUGGUGUUCUGUUAACUUCCAGCAGGAUGCAGAAUCUAACUGGUAAACCUAUAAAUUGGUCAAGUUUUACCCAUGUUGUUUCUUUGAAAACAAUGUAUAUUCUCUAAUAUUUGGAUAUAGGGUAUAUGAACAUUAAUGCAACUUAAUUGUAUUUCCAAGUACAGUACGUAUGUUCAGAUUUCUUUUUCUAACCUUAUUUAGUGAUAGAGGUGUGGUAAACUCUUCCAUUAUGUUUAUGUAUUAACACUGUAAUUUUGUCAUUUUUAUAUAUUUUGACAUUAUGUAACUAGAUGCAUACAGGAUUAGGUAUUCUGUAUUCCUUUUUAUGUGGAGAUGAUAUUUUUACAUAGCAAAGUAUUGUAAUGCAUUAAUAAUAAAUGGUCAAACAUUUAUUUAUUUAUUUAUUUAUUUUAGAUGGAGUUUCACUCUUGUCAUCAAGGGUGGAGUGCAAUGGUGCGAUCUCGGCUCACUGCAACCUUGGCCUCCCAGGUUCCAGCAAUUCUCCUGCCUCAGCCUCCUGAGUAGCUGGGAUUACAGGCACCUGCCACCACGCCCAGGUAAUUUUUUUAUAUUUUUAGUAGAGAUGGGGUUUCACCAUGUUGGCCAGGCUAGUCUCGAACUCCUGAUGGUCAGACAUUUAUAUUGCACUUCCCAUAGAUCAGGCCCCCUUCUAAAUGACAUAUAAGUAUUAACUCAGUAUGCAUUAUAAACUUAAGUAUGUAAUGUUAUUAUCCCCAGUUUACAGAUGAGAAAACUGGUAUGAUACACUUAAGUUACUUGCCUGCAUUCACUGACUGGUAAAUGGUAGAGCCAAGAUCUGAACCCAGACAGUCCAUGCACUUAACCACUACCCUAUUAACGGAGUAUGUUCUGUGUGCCAGGCAAAGUUUUGCCAUUGAAAUACUUCACCUAAUGGAGGAGGAACAGAUUAUAGAAAAAUCAAGAAAAUAUGGUAUUAUAGAGUUAUAGGAAAAAAAAGCAUUUUAGGAGAGUUAAGGGGGGUUGGGAAUAAUAAUUUUAUAUAACUAGGAAAAGAAAGCCUCUUGGUAAGGAGCAUUUGAGCGGAGAUCUCAACAAGUUGGGACAGUGAGUCAUAUGAAUUUGUCUUGCAAGAGUAGUGUUGGCAUGCAAAGGCCCACAACAAGGAGGCCAAUACAGCUGGAGUGGAACAAAGGGGUGAUGAGGGAGCAGUAAAAGAUGAUGUGGUCAGAGACAUGGUAGAUCCUGAUCUUGUUGGGUUUUCUGAGACAUUGUUAGGACUUUUCCUUAUUUCAGUGAGUUGGCACAUCAGUCAGGGUCCCAGCAGGAACUCAGGUUGACACCCACAGACUAGGACAAUUCAAGUAGAGUUUUCAUAAAGGGUCUACUCAGUCCUGUGGACAGGAUCCAGGGAAACCACAAAAAGUUGUAAAGCACCCAGCAGCUUAGCAGGGCAGAGCUCUAACACCUCACAGCCUGAAGGGACGAAGGGAGGGAGCAACUGAAUCUGGAGACGAGAGGAGAGGGCUGCAUUCCAGGAGCUGAGAGAGGUCAGUCAGCGAUAGCAUCCAGCCCCAGGUCCUCCUGCAGGAAAUAGCCAGGGUCAGACCUCACUCUCCUUCAUCCAUUGAGACAGGAAAAUAUCCCCAUUUAUGAAUAUAUAAAUCAAUAGCAGAUCCAGAGACAAUUUGGGUAUUGGAGUUAGCAGACAAAGACUUUAAAAUAACCAAGAAUAAUAUGUUAAGGGAAAUGGAGGAAACAUGGACAAACCAUAGAAAAUGAGAGACAAACUGCAAAUCUACCAAACAACCAAAGAAGAAGGACACAUUGCUUUCAAAGCAGCAUCAGUAAGACUAAUGAUGACUUUUCAAAAGAAACUAUGGAAGCAAGAAGACAAUGAAUGACAUCUGACAUAUAAAGGGUUAAAUGGGUUGGAGGAGGGGGAAAUUGUCAAUCAAAAGUUCUGUAACCUAAGAAAAUAUUCUUCAAAACUGAAGGCAACAAUGUUUUCCAAUGGGAGGGAAUAUUUUUUUUUUUUUUUUUGAGAUGGAGUCUCACUCUGUCGCCAUGCUGGAGUGCAGUGGCAUGAUCUCGGCUCACUGCAACCUCCUCCUCCUGGGUUCAAGUGAUUCUCCUGCCUCAGCCUCCUGAGUAGCUGGGACUACAGGUGUGUGCUACCACGCCCAGCUAAUUUUUGUAUUUUUAGUGGAGACAGGGUUUCACCAUGUUGGCCAGGAUGGUCUCGAUCCUUUGACCUCACAUGAUUUGCCCACCUCGGUCUCCCAAAGUGCUGGGAUUACAGGCGUGAGCCACCACGCCCGGCCUGGGAGGGAUUUUUUUAAGCUGAGAGAAUUAACAGCAUAACCGUAUUUUCAGAAACACUGAAGAGAUUUCUUCAGGCUUCAGGAAAAUGAUUCCAUAGAGACAUACAUAAUUCCAGGAAUUAAGAUCAACAGGAAACAUAAGAUGCAAGUAAAUAUAAAUCAGUACUGACUGUAUAAAACAACCCUGUAUAGUUUUACAACUUUUAUGUAUAUCUAAACUUUCCAAAAUAAAAUGCUUUUAAAAACA